GAGUCUGCAGACGGCCGUGGCUCCUCUGUUCUUCCCGAGGCUACAGCAACAGGUUCAUUCUGGGAUGGGUUGGGGGUGGGGAGGCAAAAGCCACCCUGGCAGGCCCGGACCUUUUGUAGUUUCUGUGGGACGCGCAUGGCUGACCGCCUGCAAAGAAAAACAGCGCCUCCCUUAAGGGUCAGGUCCCAGUGAGAGGACCCUGACAGCCCAGCUGGGGGUGGAACGAGGGACCCUUGUCUGCAGUGGCCAGGGUCCAAGCCCCUGGACAUGUGCUUAGGGCAGGGGACCUUCCAAAACAGCUCCUCUGAGGGAGGGGAGUGGGCACACAUGGUACCUGCCAAGUCCCCCGAGAGUCCCCUGUGAGCUGGACCAAGCCCUGUUUCCUGCUGAGGCUAGGAGAGACAGAACCGACAGCCCGCAGGCUGUGCAUGGUUAGGCCCACAUCCAGAGUAUGUGGGCUGUGCAGCUGUGCAUGCUGGGGUGGCCGUGCUGGGAGCCGUGGGUGGGUAACAGUUGGAUGUGGGGUGUAGAUGUAGGUGCCUUGUUUACCACUGUGGAUGUCUGAAAUGGGCAGGGAUGUGUGUGUGUGAGGAGAGAGAGAGAGAGAGAGAAAGAAGCUGUCCUGUGAGCCCAUGGGUGAAAUAUAACUGAUAGUGACCAUAGAAACUUUUGCGAGUGUGUGCACCUAUGUGUGUGUGCUGACAAACAGAACAGUCCUGUGUGUGUCCAUGGGUGCAACAAUGAUGAGAAUCCUUCCAUGUGACUGCGGCAGGGGCCUGUAUUGCGUGUCACUGUCCCUGUAGCAAUGAAGAACUGUCGGUGUCUGGGUCUUGAAGUGGCUGGUACACAGUCGUGUUCAAUAAAUGCUUAAGGAAUGAGUAACCGAACGCAGGGAAACUGACCUGGAGCAGGUGUCCAACGACCUGGUCUUACAAGCCUUUUCUCUAGAGGUCUGUCUGUCCACCUCCCGACAUAUGGGGUCUCCUGUCCCUCCUGGUCACCCAGCCCAGAGCCUGGCACUGUGUAGGUGCUCAUGGAAUAUUUGUUGAAUAAAGUAACCAGUGAACAAAAGAGUUCCUGGAGUACGGAGGUGGGAGAGACCCCUGUAGAGGAAACUCCCUGAAGCCCACCCUUUAGCCAGGUUCUGGGGGUGGGACAUCUGCAGAGAGCUCUGAGAAACCUGGGUUUCGGGGAGCAUCUGGAUCAGGGGAAAAGGGCACGGGCUUUGGAGCCAGGCCCGACCCAGGCCACUUCCUCACUGUGUGCUUGAGGAAGUGGCCUCACUUUGCUGAGCCUCAGAGUUCCCCUCUGUACAAUGGGGCUCCUGAUCCCACUGUCUCAGUCCACGUGGCCCAUGGCAGGUGCUCAAUGGAUGUUUGCUGAAUGACUGAAUGUCGAUCAUAAGUUACAGCCACGCCCCAUGGGCAGCAAGGCUCUGUAGCUCAUCCUGGACUCCAGUCACAUCAACACCUGGCUUCUCCCGGGUGGAUCCAGUGAACCAUUUUCUUUUGGUUUGAAGCCAGAGGUGUUCCUGGGGAGAUGGCGGAACAGCACGGAGCACCCGAACAGGCUGCAGCUGGCAAGAGCCAUGGAGACCUUGGGGGCAGCUACAAGGUGAUCUUGUACGAACUAGAGAACUUCCAAGGCAAACGCUGCGAGCUCUCGGCCGAGUGCCCCAGCCUGACCGACAGCCUGCUGGAGAAGGUGGGCUCCAUCCAAGUGGAGUCCGGGCCGUGGCUGGCAUUUGAGUCCAGGGCCUUCCGCGGGGAGCAGUUUGUUCUGGAGAAGGGGGAUUAUCCUCGCUGGGAUGCCUGGUCCAACAGCCGUGAUAGUGACAGCCUUCUGUCCCUCCGGCCUCUGAAUAUUGAUAGUCCACAUCACAAGCUGCAUCUGUUUGAGAACCCAGCUUUCAGUGGCCGCAAGAUGGAGAUAGUGGAUGAUGACGUGCCCAGCCUGUGGGCUCAUGGCUUCCAGGACCGUGUGGCGAGUGUCCGUGCCAUCAACGGGACGUGGGUUGGCUAUGAGUUCCCCGGCUACCGUGGGCGCCAGUACGUGUUUGAGCGGGGCGAGUACCGCCACUGGAAUGAGUGGGACGCCAGCCAGCCGCAGCUGCAGUCUGUGCGCCGCAUCCGUGACCAGAAGUGGCACAAGCGGGGCCGCUUCCCCAGCAGCUGAAAGGCACCCAGACUUCAAGGACCCAGACCCACCCUGGGGGGCUGCAAGGGCAAGAAGAGGAGGCUCCAGGGUUGGGGCGAGGGCCGACCUGUCCACCCUUCCCUGGAAUCUGCUCAAUAAAGCCUGGGGUUGGUCCCCCACCCGCCA